AGUCCCGGUUCCCCGCCAUCAGCACGACCUGUGUGAGAGCACAGGGUAUCUGGGCAGAAGGAAAACUAGGGGAGCCUCAUCCAGCGCUGGAGAUGGAGAAGCUUUGGGCUUCUCGACGGCGAGGCACCCGGGGAACGGGGAGUCACUUAGAACCUCAAAGUAGCCUCGGGCGAGAACAAGCGAAGCAAUUCCAAGCUCUACCAGGUCACGGAGGGCGCGAAACCCGCCCCGCGCUCCGGCCGGCCGGCAGGGGGCGCGCGCUCCCCGAACUCCCGCGCACCGCGGAGGAGGCGGCCCUGGCGCGGGGAAGCAGUGGGAAAAUCGCAAGGAAGCCGGGUAAGGACCUUUCAUUUUCAGCCCUGCUCUUUAAAUACUAGACAUACCGUCUGGCGCAUGUCGAGGCGUGUAUUAUUUUGAUCCAGUGCGCGUGCCGUAUGUGACUUGGCUUGGCUUCCCCUGAAAGCAGCGGCUGUGGGGAGUUGAUUCGGAAGUGAAGGGCCCUGGGCGACCCGGCGAGUAGAGGCAACACCAACACUCCUCCUUAGCGAGGGGUCUCCCCGCCGCGGUGGCUGCCCGGCCCCAAGGACAGGAGGGAUUUGUGCACUGACUCCUGACCCCGUCCUCCAGCGCUGCUCUGAAGGGAGAGUCUGUGCAGUGGCACCUGCGCGAAGCUGGCCAAAGCCUGCCCAGACGGCUCACCUGUGCGGGAUGGAACAAAAGGUCGGCCAGGAGCGCGCCGGUAAGAGCCUGGGGGCAAGGGGUAGAAAGACGCCCACCUCAUCACAACCCAGAGCUCGGGACUCCUAUACAGUCCCAUAGGGAACAGGCGGCCGCCAUUCCCCUCCCCCACGCUGGCGGUUUGUUUCGACGCCGGACCGCGUAAGAGACGAUGAUGUUGGGCACGGAAGGUGGAGAGGGAUUCGUGGUGAAGGUCCGGGGCUUGCCCUGGUCUUGCUCGGCCGAUGAAGUGCAGAGGUUUUUUUCUGACUGCAAAAUUCAAAAUGGGGCUCAAGGUAUUCGUUUCAUCUACACCAGAGAAGGCAGACCAAGUGGCGAGGCUUUUGUUGAACUUGAAUCAGAAGAUGAAGUCAAAUUGGCCCUGAAAAAAGACAGAGAAACUAUGGGACACAGAUAUGUUGAAGUAUUCAAGUCAAACAACGUUGAAAUGGAUUGGGUGUUGAAGCAUACUGGUCCAAAUAGUCCUGACACGGCCAAUGAUGGCUUUGUACGGCUUAGAGGACUUCCCUUUGGAUGUAGCAAGGAAGAAAUUGUUCAGUUCUUCUCAGGGUUGGAAAUCGUGCCAAAUGGGAUAACAUUGCCGGUGGACUUCCAGGGGAGGAGUACGGGGGAGGCCUUCGUGCAGUUUGCUUCACAGGAAAUAGCUGAAAAGGCUCUAAAGAAACACAAGGAAAGAAUAGGGCACAGGUAUAUUGAAAUCUUUAAGAGCAGUAGAGCUGAAGUUAGAACUCAUUAUGAUCCACCACGAAAGCUUAUGGCCAUGCAGCGGCCAGGUCCUUAUGACAGACCUGGGGCUGGUAGAGGGUAUAACAGCAUUGGCAGAGGAGCUGGCUUUGAGAGGAUGAGGCGUGGUGCUUAUGGUGGAGGCUAUGGAGGCUAUGAUGAUUACAAUGGCUAUAAUGAUGGCUAUGGAUUUGGGUCAGAUAGAUUUGGAAGAGACCUCAAUUACUGUUUUUCAGGAAUGUCUGAUCACAGAUACGGGGAUGGUGGCUCUACUUUCCAGAGCACAACAGGACACUGUGUACACAUGCGGGGAUUACCUUACAGAGCUACUGAGAAUGACAUUUAUAAUUUUUUUUCACCGCUCAACCCUGUGAGAGUACACAUUGAAAUUGGUCCUGAUGGCAGAGUAACUGGUGAAGCAGAUGUCGAGUUCGCAACUCAUGAAGAUGCUGUGGCAGCUAUGUCAAAAGACAAAGCAAAUAUGCAACACAGAUAUGUAGAACUCUUCUUGAAUUCUACAGCAGGAGCAAGCGGUGGUGCUUACGAACACAGAUAUGUAGAACUCUUCUUGAAUUCUACAGCAGGAGCAAGCGGUGGUGCUUAUGGUAGCCAAAUGAUGGGAGGCAUGGGCUUGUCAAACCAGUCCAGCUACGGGGGCCCAGCCAGCCAGCAGCUGAGUGGGGGUUACGGAGGCGGCUACGGUGGCCAGAGCAGCAUGAGUGGAUACGACCAAGUUUUACAGGAAAACUCCAGUGAUUUUCAAUCAAACAUUGCAUAGGUAACCAAGGAGCAGUGAACAGCAGCUACUACAGUAGUGGAAGCCGUGCAUCUAUGGGCGUGAACGGAAUGGGAGGGUUGUCUAGCAUGUCCAGUAUGAGUGGUGGAUGGGGAAUGUAAUUGAUCGAUCCUGAUCACUGACUCUUGGUCAACCUUUUUUUUUUUUUUUUUUUUUUCUUUAAGAAAACUUCAGUUUAACAGUUUCUGCAAUACAAGCUUGUGAUUUAUGCUUACUCUAAGUGGAAAUCAGGAUUGUUAUGAAGACUUAAGGCCCAGUAUUUUUGAAUACAAUACUCAUCUAGGAUGUAACAGUGAAGCUGAGUAAACUAUAACUGUUAAACUUAAGUUCCAGCUUUUCUCAAGUUAGUUAUAGGAUGUACUUAAGCAGUAAGCGUAUUUAGGUAAAAGCAGUUGAAUUAUGUUAAAUGUUGCCCUUUGCCACGUUAAAUUGAACACUGUUUUGGAUGCAUGUUGAAAGACAUGCUUUUAUUUUUUUGUAAAACAAUAUAGGAGCUGUGUCUACUAUUAAAAGUGAAACAUUUUGGCAUGUUUGUUAAUUCUAGUUUCAUUUAAUAACCUGUAAGGCACGUAAGUUUAAGCUUUUUUUUUUUUUAAGUUAAUGGGAAAAAUUUGAGACGCAAUACCAAUACUUAGGAUUUUGGUCUUGGUGUUUGUAUGAAAUUCUGAGGCCUUGAUUUAAAUCUUUCAUUGUAUUGUGAUUUCCUUUUAGGUAUAUUGCGCUAAGUGAAACUUGUCAAAUAAAUCCUCCUUUUAAAAACUGCA